AGUGUGUGUGGGGCUUCCGCUGAGACCUGCCGUGCUGGGUGGUGAGUGGGCUGUGAGCUGACCACGGACCCCUGCCCUCCAGCCUCUGACCUCUGGGAGCCAGGGCUGUGUGACCCUGCAGUGCUGGGUGGCGGGUGGGCUAUGAGCUGACCGCGGACCCCCAUUCUCCAGCCUGCGGUCUGUGGGAGCCAGGGCUGUGUGGCCCUGCACUGGCCAUGUGCUUCUGAUGGGUGUGUUUUGCCUCCUGUCCUUUGCGGAGAUGGAGCAUUUUCCCUGGCCAAGUUGCCCCUUCUCUGUGGGGCGCCUCUGAGGAUGAGUCAGGCAGUGACUCAGGACCGCAGAGCUCAGCCCAGAGGCUGGCUUGGGAGCCCCAGGGCUGCUUCGCAGACCCGGUUUGGGGUUUGGUUCCUCUUCACGCAGCCUUUACCCUCUACCCCGAGGCUGGGGCAGCCCUGGCAGCUCCCGGCUCCCCCCAGCGUUUGGGAAAUGGGCCCCGAGCCUGCGGCAGAGCACAGAGCUGGGAAACCAGGUUUAUUUUCUUAUGAUCACGUGAUGGGAGCAGCCGCAGGCGGGAUGGGGCAGCGCCAGCCUUGCGCAGAUGCUGGGAAGUGACUCAGGGAGGAGAAGGCGGGGGUUUCUCUGCUGGUCCCAGCUGAGCCCCUGCUCCAGGCUCCAGGAGGAGGAGGAAUUCAGUUCAGAUGGUUUCCCCUCAUCAGAGCCACUACUUAAAGGUCAACUCUGUUUUCUGCAAGAGGUUUUUUCUUUUUUCCCCGUGAAAGUUUGCUUGAUUCUGUGAAACUUCAUUUGCACUUCUUCCAGAAAUGACUGAGGGAAAGGAGACUUUGCCAGGGUCUCUGCCUCAGAGGGAGAGGCUGCUGCGUGCGUUAAUUUCCUUAGGCCACAUGGCAGGAUUUCAGGCGAGCCUGGUCCUCUCAGGCCGCACUUUUUCUUUAUUUGGAAAGAGAGUUCCAGAGCCCUCGGGCGGUGAGUGGGGGCCGCCUGGGCCAGGCAUUCAUCCCGCAUCUGACUGCUGCUGACCUCGGCUGGAGACAAAGCCGGCCUGUCCAAGAGAUACCCCGAGGUUAAGCUGCUGAUGGGAAGGGGGGCACCUGGUGGCUGUGUGGCCCCUUUGAGUCCAUCAGAAAGAAGAGAUUGUCCGGCACAGGCCACCGAACAGGAUGGGGGAUGGGAGGAAUGCCCUAGCGUUCAGCCGGUUUCAUUUUUCUUUUGGAAUACGCUUCAAACUCUGCUGCCCAGGAAGGAGAAAGCACAAACCUUCCUGCUGAUGAAAGAAAAUGGGUGCCCCCACCAUGAGACCCACGGACAGCGGGGGGCUGUCCGUGGGCCUGGGCUUUGCACCUGGGAGUGUUGGUGCUGUGUGGAGGGAACUGACCCUGUCCUCAGGCUGAGCCUGGAGUCCCCACAACAGCAUAGGGGGGAAAGCUGCUGUCCUCAGACUCCGCGUGGCCUCCAGUGAUGGUGCUGUGGCCACUUCCUGCCGGGUGCUCACCGUGGGUUCUGGGUGGGGCUGGGAGGACAUGGGGCGUAGGCCAUUCUGCCCACGAGGUGACGUGAUCGAGGUGGACGUGGCUGGCCUCGCAGCCUCUGCUCCUGCAGGUCCUGGGACGCUGUGUCCAUCUGCUGGAGCUCAUUUCAGAGUUGGCUGAUCACAGGUCCAUAGUCACCCACUGGUGACAAAUUUAACAAAUUUGUGGGGGUUUUUUUAGUUCAAAAAAGAUCCUCCUUAAAUGUUGUGAAAUAAUAUGUCUUUUAAGUUGCAACACACAUUCAGAAGUUCCCGGAGGGUUAAAUCCUGAGCAUGAAAAGAUGGUCAUUCUAAUAGAAAACAGGCCCAGAGCAUUUCAAGAAAAAAUGAGAUUUAAAACUGCUCAUAAAAAGAUGGACAUUCCACCUCACCAAUGAGCCAGACAUUUAAAAUUUAAGCAGGUUUUUGCCACCGGUUUAGCAAACUGUAGAAAUAUUUAUAAGACGGCGUAUGCUGGGGGUGGACACUGGUCCAGACUCCCUGGAGGGUUCUGUGGCUUUGUGUUUCAAAGGCCUCAGGACAGUGCACAUCCUUGGAGGAAUUUAUCCCACGGGGACAAUCAGCCACUGCACAGAUCUGCGUUCCCAGGGUGCUCACCCCUGCUGCUCCCACCACACAGCGUGCACAUGGCAGGGGGACCUGGCACUGCUGUCCACGCACACACGUGCCGUCUGACCCCAGCGUUUUAUCAGCUCUUUGGAAAGUGGCCCAUGGCCUGAUGUGAAAGGAAAAAGCUGACUCUGUCACAGGGAACAUAACCUCACUUUUAUUUAAAAAAUUUAUCCGUAUUUCCAUUCGUAUCUUCUAUAUUUAUAACAUAAAUAUUUACUAUUAUUGUUAAUAUAUUUGUAUUAUAAUAUAAUGAGUCAUUAUAGUAUGAAUAUACUUAUAUUUGUAUUAUAAAUAUUGUAUUUAUGUUAUAAAUGUAAUACAAAUAUAUUUAUAUUUUGUAUAUUUUAAACCUAUAACAUUUAUAUAUUUUAUUCUAUUUUAUAUUUUUGGAGAAAAAACUCCAGGAGGAUGUUUCCUGGAAUGUUAAUUCCAGAUUUCACUUUCUGAUUUUUUUACGUAUUUAAAAUUUUGUUUCUUUAAAAAUAGCUUUAUUGAGGUAUAAUUCAAGCACCGUACAAUUCACCCAUUUUGAAAUGUACAAUUCAGUGGUUUUUAGUAUAUUUGCAGAGUUGUGCAACAAUUGCCACAGCCAAUUUUAGAACAUUUUCAUCUCCCUAAAACGACACUCGCGCCCUGUAAUCCUCCAGUUUCCGGCCUGCAGCCUCUCCUGGGGCGGCAGACACGGGUCCCCGUUCUGUCGCCGGCUGUGCCUCUCUUGGGCAUUUCGUGUCAGUGGAAGCGUCUGGCCCAUGGCCUCUGUGUGCGUGGCCUGUUGGUUGGCACCACAUUGUGGAUGCUGUGGUGUGGGGCCAGGGUCCAGGCGUCCUUCCUCUCCAGGGCUGAGCACCGUUCUGCUGUUGCUCCCUCAGCAGCCGAGGCCCACCUGCCUUGUUUCCACUGUCUGGCUGUCAUGACUGAGGCUGUGAGCACGCAUGUCUGAGUCUGCGUGCGAACGUGGGCUGUGAGCACGCGUGUCCGAGUCUGCAUGCGGACGUGGGCUGUGAGCACGCGUGUCCGAGUCUGCAUGCGGACGUGGGCUGUGAGCACGCGUGUCUGAGUCUGCGUGCGGACGUGGGCUGUGAGCACGCGUGUCCGAGUCUGCGUGCGGACGUGGGCUGUGAUGUCUAUUGCUGCACACCUGGGGGUGGAACCACUGUGUCCCGUGGCGACUGUGUGUUGAACGUCGGAGGAACCGCCAGCCUGUUUUCCGUGGCGGCUGUGGCCACUUGACCUUUGCACAAGUUGUGUGUUUGGAUUCGCAUCUCCACCUCCCUACCCUUGUUACUGUCUCUUUGAUCACAGCCAUCCCGGUGGGUCUGAUUUUCUUUGUACAAUGCGAGCCCCCCCUCAAUGAAUUUUUGCUUAAAAAAAAGCAAUUUGUUGUUUUUAAUUGAAAUGAAAGGAAGCAUUCUUUCCUAUGCAUGUGUUUUUUUUAAAGCAAACAAAAUUAAAAUCAUAAGUAAGUAAAAAAAAAACCCACAGGAAAAUUCUAAAAACUUGCACAUAAAUGGAAUUACGAAUCAACUCAUCGUGGAAAAUCGUGUCUUGCUGGAUGUAGGUUAUAGAUGUAAGGUUAGGCACAGUGGAAAGGGAGAUGGAACCUGCAGACCCCAGACGUGGACAUGGUCCAGGACGGCGUCAGUCCGACCCCCGCCUUUUCUGCCCACCGUGGGAUCUGGAGCCCCCUGCCCACCAUGUCCCCUGAGCUGGCUUGACCUUGCCGUCCUCCCCGCCCAACCCCUGCGCCGUGUGCUCUGUGCAGACACGUCCCCUGUUGAGUCUGAGAUGGAGUUACCACCGCAAGCACAGGUGACGGCUGAAUCCCACUGCCGCCUCCGUGGAUAGGGCACCAGAAACCCUCUGGAGAGAAGGCAGCCUGCCACGCUUUGUAAUGAGCAGUUCGCUUAAGGAUCGUGUUAGACUCCAUGGCUAGUAUAGAUUUCAAAGCUCGUAUUUCUUUCUUUCUUUUUCUUUUUUUUUUUUUUUUGAGACAGAGUCUUGCUUUGUCGCCCAGGCUGGAGUGCAGUGGUGCGAUCUCGGUUCACUGCAACCUCCGCCUCCCAGGUUCAAGUGAUUCUCCUGCCUCAGCCUCCUGAGUAGCUGGGAUUACAGGCGCCUGCCGCCAUGCCCAGUAAUUUUUUUUUUUUUUGUAUUUUUAGUAGAGACGGCGUUUCACCAUGUUGGCCAGGAUGCUCUCAAUCUCUUGACCUCAUGAUCCACCCACCUUGGCCUCCCAAAGGGCUCCUGUUUCAUAACCCAUCACCCUUAAAGAGCCGUUCUCUGAGGUGGGCCUGGGCGCCUGGGGUUUUUAGAAACCUUUUCAGGCAACCGUAGUUUGCGGUUCUAAGAGGAAAAACAUCAAGAGACCUGAAGAACCCAAGCCCCACGCAUCAAGGCAGCGUCCCCGGCCAUGGCGGAGGGAGCCCCGCGCAUCGAGGCAGCGUCCCCGGCCGUGGCGGGGGUGGAGAAGGGAGAACUGAGUUGGGUUUUGGUGUGGCUAUUUCUGUGGUAUUCCCUCGAAAUAUUUGCCACUGAAAAAAUGAAAAAACUCUAAGUGCUUUUAAGUGAGUAAUUUCUGUGCGAGGUCUCGGGAAGAAGAAAUGUCUCUGUGUGCAGUGCCCAGGCUCCAUCUGCCGGCUGUGGGGGCUCCGUCUGCCGGCUGUGGGGGGCUCCGUCUGCCGGCUGUGGGGGGCUCCAUCUGCCGGCUGUGGGGGGCUCCGUCUGCCGGCUGUGGGGGCUCCGUCUGCCGGCUUUGGAGGCCCCGUCUCCCGGCUGUGGAGGUGGCAGAGCCUGGCUGGGGUCUUCCCGAGGGCCCAGCCUCCUGCUCUUCACAGGGAGCCUCAGGGAAGGUGAGGCCUCUGCCUCCCUUUCAAGCCACUGGACUUGAGCUGACCACUGAUAACACUGCAGCUCCACCGCGGGCGAGCGCAGCGCUGGGGGACAGUCCUGGCCUGAGCUCCGGGCGUGCGCGGCUCCAGCUGCGUCCUGCCCGCCUCUCGCCUCACUGGAAGCAGAGCGGAACGGGGCGUGUCCGGUCCUGGCCCUUCGCGUCCCCGCAGGCCCGUCACCUCCUGCAGGAGCCCCUCUGGCUUCCCGGCAGUCUUGGCUCUGCCAGAACUGAAUUCCUGUCGUCCCCAUGAGGACAACCAGGAUUUGCUCGGCACCGUGGCCUCUCGGGCUGACCGCUGCACCUUGCUUGCAGAAAGCCCCACCUGUGGAGGCUUGGGUGACCUUCCCUUCCUGGUCCACUGUGCCAGGUCUGGGCAGCUCCUGGCUGCUGACCUGAGACAGGUGAUUCCUCCCUGCAUGCCCACUGCCCCAUCCGUGCAUCCGUCCAUCCAGUGUCUUGCACGGGCCUGCAUAUUCCCAGCUGCUGUGGUGAAAUGUCUGCUCUGCACCACGUGACCUCGGCUGCACCCUGACCUCUGACCUCGGCUCCCAGCAUGCUCCGGUCCUGCCGUGCCCUGCCCAGGCCACGUCAGCCUUCUCCUUGCUCCUACGUCUUUACCACACACAAGCCCUGCUGCCUCGAGGCCUUCGCACCUGGUGUCCCUCUGCCUAGACCCCUCCUGCGCUCUCCGCGCCGUCCAUGGCCUCAUUCAUGCGUUCCCUUGUCCUCCUGCGGGUCUCCUCACCGUCCACAGCGCUGUUCAAGCGCUCACUCGUCCGUAAGCCUCCCUGUCCCCCGAGCGAGGCCACAGUGCUGCCCCCGCCAGCCUUGCCCGCGUUGGACAUUCGUGGUUCUGUGUGCUCUUUGGCUGGCUCCAUGGGGCCAGGACUUUGCUUCAUUGGCUGCUAUUCCCACAGUCUAGAACGGGGAUGGGCAGCUGAAACAGUCAUGGAGAGAGAGAGCGCUGUGGUUUCUGGGUCCAGUGAGCCACGCCUGGCGGGGGCCAAAGACAUCGAAAGUGCUCCCCGUUGUUUGGUCCUGGUGUGUGGGAGGCCCUGCCAUGUGCUUGUCUCACUGUGCAGGGCAGAGGAAGAAACCUCCAAGCCAGGCAGUGGUGUGUCCUGGGGAGGCCGCUUUGGGGGCAGAGCCACUGCCCUUCCCCAGCCGAGCGCCCUCUGUGCCCGCAGGCUGCACUGUGGAGAGGGCGGUGUCCUGAGGCUGAGAGAUGAGGGAACUGGCCUCUGGCAAGGCAGCGUUGAAACGUGGACGUCCCCAUCUUCAAAGUCGUGCUUCCCCCGGCAAGGCCCGUGUGGGCACCUGUGCCUCCUGGGUACCUGUGCCUCCUGGGUACCUGCGCCUCCUCGCAUUGGCUUCAGCGACGUCUGUCACAGAUUCUUACAUUUAGACGUGCCAUAUAGUCUUCCUGGUGGAGACCAACGUCCCCUUGGCCUUGUGAAGCUUACCAGGGCCUGAAUUAGGUUGGGGGGAGCAGCUGCACCUGGGGACUGUGCUGUGAAGAUGCAGGAGGGCCUGACGGCGGCUCCUCCAGGCGGGACUGUGCUCUGAAGAUGCAGGAGAUGCAGGUGUUUGGUUUUUUGAGACAGGAUCUCGCCCUGUCACUCAGGCAGGAGUGCAGUGCUGUGAUCACAGCUCACUGCAGCCUGGAACCCCGGGCUCAAGCAAUCCUCCGCUUCGCUGCAGACGUGCGCCACCAAACCCAUCUAAUUUUUAAAUUUUCUGUUGAGUUGGGGUCUUGCUAUGUUGCCCAGGUUGAUCUCUAACUCCUGGGCUCAAGUGGCGCUUCUGGCAUGGCCUCCCAAAGUGCUGGGAUUACAGGCGUGAGCCACUGCAUCUGGCCUGGAUGCAGGUAUUUAAAAGAGCUUAGGGAAGUUCUUCGAAAAAGGCUCUGGCCUUCAACUCCCACUUCUACUCCUGAUUUUGGUUCUCAUUGGGAUAUAAGUUUCAGAGCACUCCUGGGCUCAGGAGAAGAGCAGCUCCCCUGCGAGGGGCAGGGUCACCUGUGUCCACAGCAGCAGGACUUGGUCCCUGGGGACUGCGGGUCGGCAUAGUCCAGGGUGCCCAUGACCAGUCCUCCGAGGAGCAGGGCCUGGGAAGGGCAUUGUCGGGCAGGCGAGGACGGGCAUGGUUGCUGGUCUGGGCAUCAGUGGCAUUGCUCUGAGAGGGAAGGAGAUGCUGUCCCAGCAAGGGUGGCCUCAGGUCUGGACCCUCAAGUGGACACCGUGUUUUGGCUCUAGGACUGGCAUGGCCCAACAGGAUUUUCUGCAAAACAGGAAAUGGUCUCUGUGUUUUCCGUCCGGUCUGGUGACCACAAGUCACGGGCUGGUGAGCACCCGAGGAGCUGAAUUCUGUGGUGGGAAUCCAGGUUCGGGAGAGGUCGUCAGGCAGGUGUGCAGACAACGUGAGUGGUGAGCCUCACGCCCGAGGAAUCCGCUCUUCCUGCUGGACGCGUGGAUGGUGGUGACGGCCUCGCCGCAGCAGCAGCACCUGGAGCUGGCCCCUGCCGGAGACUGGCUCCAGCUUUCCUUGAAAUCCUGCAGAGCCUUCAUUAAAAUGAGUGCAAGGCCUGUAGCACGGCCGCCUCUCCGGACCCCACUGCCCUGCAAUGCCUUCUGCUCGUCCAGCUCGUGGGAAUGAAGCUUGGUCACAGUGGUUGGUGGCUCAGAGCUCCGUUGAUAAGGCUGGCCGGCCGCCUGCAGAUGUCCUGCCUGGUUUCCUGAAAGACUUGAGGUGACCCGCAGGAAACAAACACCUCAAUUUCCACGGACAGCUGUCAGCACCACCAGAAGCCUCACGGGACCCUCCCAGGUGCCCAGCCAGCACGGGCCUCCCCCCACCGAGCCCCCCACUGCCAAGCAGAGUUACAGAGAGAGGAGCCACUUGUGCAGAGCCUUUGGCAGAGCAACUGAACACCCCGCUACCGGGCAGCGCCCAGGGACGCCGCACUCUCAGCCCUGCUGCCCAAGCCCUGGGCCCGUUUUACGGAGAAGACUUUUACUGUGAAAUUCCUCGGAGCUUUCGUCACCUGUCCUUCUACAUUUUCGAUAGAGACGUUUUCCGGAGGGAUUCCAUCAUAGGGAAGGUGGCCAUCCAGAAGGAGGACUUGCAGAAGUACCACAACAGGGACACCUGGUUCCAGCUGCAGCACGUGGACGCUGACUCGGAAGUGCAGGGCAAAGUGCACCUGGAGCUGCGGCUGAGCGAGGUCAUCACAGACACUGGGGUCGUCUGCCACAAGCUCGCCACACGCAUCGUCGAGUGCCAGGGCCUCCCCAUCGUGAAUGGGCAAUGUGACCCCUACGCCACCGUGACGCUGGCAGGACCCUUCAGAUCAGAAGCAAAGAAGACGAAAGUGAAGAGGAAGACCAACAAUCCCCAGUUCGAUGAAGUGUUUUAUUUUGAGGUGACCCGGCCCUGUAGCUACAGCAAGAAGUCCCACUUUGACUUUGAGGAGGAAGACGUGGACAAGCUCGAAAUCAGAGUUGACCUCUGGAAUGCCAGUAACCUGAAGUUUGGAGAUGAAUUCCUGGGAGAACUAAGGAUCCCGUUGAAAGUCCUGCGGCAGUCCAGCUCCUACGAGGCGUGGUACUUCCUCCAGCCCCGGGACAAUGGUAGCAAGAGCCUAAAGCCAGACGACCUGGGCUCCCUGCGGCUGAACGUGGUAUACACGGAAGACCACGUGUUUUCUUCUGACUAUUACAGCCCUCUGCGGGACCUGCUGUUGAAGUCUGCGGAUGUGGAGCCCGUGUCAGCGUCUGCGGCCCACAUCCUGGGCGAGGUUUGCCGGGAGAAGCAGGAGGCGGCCGUCCCGCUGGUGCGGCUCUUCCUACACUAUGGCAGGGUGGUGCCAUUCAUCAGUGCCAUCGCCAGCGCGGAGGUGAAGCGGACCCAGGACCCCAACACCAUCUUCCGAGGAAACUCACUGGCGUCCAAGUGCAUCGACGAGACCAUGAAGCUGGCGGGGAUGCAUUACCUGCAUGUCACCCUGAAGCCCGCCAUCGAGGAGAUAUGCCAGAGCCACAAACCCUGUGAAAUCGACCCUGUGAAGUUGAAAGACGGAGAAAACCUUGAAAACAACAUGGAGAACCUACGGCAGUAUGUGGACCGCGUCUUCCACGCCAUCACUGAGUCUGGGGUGAGCUGCCCGACCGUCAUGUGUGACAUCUUCUUCUCCCUCCGGGAGGCGGCGGCCAAGCGCUUCCAGGAUGACCCGGACGUCAGGUACACUGCAGUGAGCAGCUUCAUCUUCCUGAGGUUCUUUGCGCCCGCCAUUCUCUCCCCCAACCUCUUCCAGCUCACGCCGCACCACACGGACCCCCAGACGUCCAGGACGCUGACAUUGAUCUCCAAGACCGUUCAGACCCUCGGCAGCCUGUCCAAGUCCAAAUCUGCGAGUUUUAAGGAGUCCUACAUGGCUACAUUUUAUGAAUUCUUCAAUGAGCAGAAAUAUGCUGAUGCGGUGAAGAACUUCUUGGAUCUGAUUUCGUCCUCGGGGAGAAGAGACCCCAAGAGUGUUGAGCAGCCCAUCGUGCUUAAAGAAGGGUUCAUGAUCAAGAGGGCCCAAGGACGGAAGCGCUUUGGGAUGAAGAAUUUUAAGAAGAGAUGGUUUCGCUUGACCAACCAUGAAUUUACCUACCACAAAAGCAAAGGGGACCAGCCUCUCUACAGCAUUCCCAUCGAGAACAUCCUGGCAGUGGAGAAGCUGGAGGAGGAGUCUUUCAAAAUGAAAAACAUGUUCCAGGUCAUCCAGCCAGAGCGUGCGCUGUACAUCCAGGCCAACAACUGCGUGGAGGCCAAGGACUGGAUCGACAUUCUCACCAAAGUGAGCCAGUGCAACCAGAAGCGCCUCACCGUCUACCACCCGUCCGCCUACCUGAGCGGCCACUGGCUGUGCUGUAGGGCGCCAUCCGACUCGGCUCCGGGCUGCUCGCCCUGCACUGGCGGCCUCCCAGCCAACAUCCAGCUGGACAUUGAUGGGGACCGUGAGACGGAGCGUAUCUACUCCCUCUUCAACUUGUACAUGAGCAAGCUGGAGAAGAUGCAGGAGGCCUGUGGGAGCAAAUCUGUGUAUGACGGCCCGGAGCAGGAGGAGUAUUCGACGUUCGUCAUUGACGACCCCCAGGAGACCUACAAGACGCUAAAGCAAGUCAUCGCUGGGGUUGGGGCUUUGGAGCAGGAGCACGCCCAGUAUAAGAGGGACAAGUUCAAGAAGACGAAAUAUGGAAGCCAGGAGCACCCCAUCGGAGACAAGAGCUUCCAGAACUACAUCCGGCAGCAGUCCGAGACCUCCACUCAUUCCAUUUAAAGUCUGCGGGACGCGCCCAGUGGCGCCAGCAAGCUGCCCAUGCAAAGCCGCAGCCUUUGGGAGGGAGAAGAGAAGGAAGAGCGCAGAGCCGGCAAAGUGAGAUGCACGCCGUCCCGGCCCAUAGACAAGUGGCGCUGGGGUUUCCCUCUCCCAGAACCGCUGCCACCACCGCCACGCCCUCCGCAGAAAGCCCACCUGGCCCUGUGGAACGUGUCGUCAUUUGAUUCUGUGCUUUUUGCUCCUUGUUUGUGGGGAUCUGGGGAUCAGCUGAAGGAUCAGGAAGUGUGGGCUGUGCCCUAGCCACACCACAGCCAGCCUCAGGGAGCCACGGCCCGUCUAGUCGACUGUGACAUGCACCUCCGGCCGUGUGUGCGUCAGUCUCGUGCACGUCUGUCUUGCGUGCACGGUGCGUGUGACGCUGGGCUCUGUGGCUCUGUGCCCGGGAGGCCUGCUGGCCCCGCCUCGGCUUUCGGCUUCAUCACAUUGGGAGGUUCAGAGCAUUACUCUCCCACUGUGCCUGCCAUCCAGGCAGCCAUGGGAGGCGGCCUCCCUGUUCCACUUUCGAGGUUCGUUUGAUUCCUGGCUGAGGGGUCAGUUUUAUGGCUGGGAGGUGCAGAAUUACACAGAAGUCCCAGUCUGAGGAUGUCCUUGGUGCUUGGGGGAUACGGGUUCUGUCCACAGAGUCCCUUGGAGGGAAAGGUGUGGGCUCCAGCUUCUCCAGGCGUCUGCGGAGCCCACAGUUGAAGCCCACAUCGUUUUGCUGUUGAAUGGGGUUUAAAAUCAGAAUUAACAUUUGCCACCCCCCGUGGAAGUUUGAAGAUUUUAAAAAUAGAAAUGUACAUUUUUCAAGCUGUUUUUCUUUAUGUUUUUGAAGGACCAUUUUUAAUUAGCUCUUUGAUACAAAGUAACUCAGAACGUCAAAACCUAUACCCACUAAAGGGAAGGCUGCCGGGAAGGCAAAUGGAACAGGAAUGGAGCCUGUCUCAGGAAGGCCAGCUGCAGGUCCUCCAGAAAAUCAAAGAAGGGAAGAAACUCUGAGUUUGAGGUACAGGGGCUUCGGGGUGCAGACGUCCCUCCAGGGCCCAUGGUCAGUAUUGCACCUGUGUUAUGAACCCCCAGAUGCUGUGCAGGGCAGGGGCGGGGGCUGCUGUUUUAUUGGGGAGGGGAGCAUCCUAAAAAUGGGGUCCAGGCAGACCCCUCCAGACCUCACACUGCCGAGGAGGCCUUUCCCAAAGGGCGUCCUCCCGGGAUGCAGACGGCAGGUGUGUGGGAAGCGCCGUUUAAAUACACAGCACGACGUAUCCUUGUACCGACUUCUCCCGGUUCUUGUUUGAAAAUACUGUAGUUCAGGCUCUUGAUCUAGAUGGCAGAUAGGAACUUUCUUGUCACAAAAAUACUGGAGGAAAAUGUUGUAAAAAUAGACUUUUGGACACACAGCUGUUGGGGCUGCACUGAGCUGCAAUUUUUAACAUGGAUUUAUAACUUAAUGUUUCUGUUUAUAAAAUACUAAUGAUUUGCAAUGUAUUUUACUGGCCAAUUAAAACAGAUGUUUUAUUCUUUCUGA